ACAGUCUCACCAUGGCCCGCACCGUGGUGCUCAUCACCGGCUGUUCCUCGGGCAUCGGCCUGCACUUGGCCGUACGUCUGGCUUCAGAUCCAUCCCAGAGCUUCAAAGUGUAUGCCACGUUGAGGGACCUGAAAACACAGGGCCGGCUGUGGGAGGCGGCCCGGGCCCUGGCAUGCCCUCCGGGAUCCCUGGAGACGUUGCAGCUGGACGUAAGGGACUCAAAAUCCGUGGCCGCUGCCCGGGAACGCGUGACUGAGGGCCGCGUGGACGUGCUGGUGUGUAACGCAGGCCUGGGCCUGCUGGGGCCGCUGGAGGCGCUGGGGGAGGACGCCGUGGCCUCUGUGCUGGACGUGAAUGUAGUAGGGACUGUGCGGAUGCUGCAGGCCUUCCUGCCAGACAUGAAGAGGCGCGGUUCGGGACGCGUGUUGGUGACCGGGAGCGUGGGAGGAUUGAUGGGGCUGCCUUUCAAUGACGUUUAUUGCGCCAGCAAGUUCGCGCUCGAAGGCUUAUGCGAGAGUCUGGCGGUUCUGCUGCUGCCCUUUGGGGUCCACAGCUUGAGCCUGAUCGAGUGCGGCCCAGUGCACACCGCCUUCAUGGAGAAGGUGUUGGGCAGCCCAGAGGAGGUGCUGGACCGCACGGACAUCCACACCUUCCACCGCUUCUACCAAUACCUCGCCCACAGCAAGCAAGUCUUUCGCGAGGCGGCGCAGAACCCUGAGGAGGUGGCGGAGGUCUUCCUCACCGCUUUGCGCGCCCCGAAGCCGACCCUGCGCUACUUCACCACCGAGCGCUUCCUGCCCCUGCUGCGGAUGCGCCUGGACGACCCCAGCGGCUCCAACUACGUCACCGCCAUGCACCGGGAAGUGUUCGGCGACGUUCCGGCAAAGGCCGAGGCUGGGGCCGAGGCUGGGGGCGGGGCCGGGCCUGGGGCAGAGGACGAGGCCGGGCGCGGUGCGGUGGGGGACCCUGAGCUCGGCGAUCCUCCGGCCGCCCCGCAGUAAAGGCUUCCUCAGCCGCUGUCUCCCGCGCCCUUCUUUGUCCCCUGGGUCUGUGUGGUCCCUGGGGAUGGGGCGGCGGUAGCAGCUGUGGGUGGCUAAUUAAGAUAGAUCGCGUUAGCCAGUUUUACCAGCGCAGCUAGGCGCGAUGGCUGUCGCCUGUAAUGCCAGCGCUUUGGGAGGCGGAGGCAGGAGGAUCGCUCAAGCCCCGGAGUUGGAGACCAGCCAGAGCAACACAGUGAGACCCCCAUCUCUACAAAAAUAAAGAAAAUUUAAAAAUCA